AUAACUCCCAAACGGCAAGUUUCUACAAAGUUACAACAGUGGGGAGGCGCCACAACUUCACUGCCAUUUUGUGAGGUGCUGCCGCCCCUCCUCCGGCAAGAUCUCCUAUUCACCUCAAAUAAAUUUUCAUGGAAUGGAGUAAAGUCAGAGUCCGGGUAUAUUUUAUGUGAUUACUAAAGGAAACAAUGACCGAUAAAACAGAGAAGGUGGCUGUAGAUCCUGAAACUGUGUUUAAACGUCCCAGGGAAUGUGACAGUCCUUCGUAUCAGAAAAGGCAGAGGAUGGCCCUGUUGGCAAGGAAACAAGGAGCAGGAGACAGCCUUAUUGCAGGCUCUGCCAUGUCCAAAGAAAAGAAGCUUAUGACAGGACAUGCUAUUCCACCCAGCCAAUUGGAUUCUCAGAUUGAUGACUUCACUGGUUUCAGCAAAGAUGGGAUGAUGCAGAAACCUGGUAGCAAUGCACCUGUGGGAGGAAACGUUACCAGCAAUUUCUCUGGAGAUGACCUAGAAUGCAGAGGAAUAGCCUCCUCUCCCAAAAGCCAACAAGAAAUUAAUGCUGAUAUAAAAUGUCAAGUAGUGAAGGAAAUCCGAUGCCUUGGACGAAAAUAUGAAAAAAUCUUCGAAAUGCUUGAAGGAGUGCAAGGACCUACUGCAGUCAGGAAACGAUUUUUUGAAUCCAUCAUCAAGGAAGCAGCAAGAUGUAUGAGACGAGACUUUGUUAAGCACCUUAAGAAGAAACUGAAACGUAUGAUUUGAGAAUACUUGUCCCUGGAGGAUUAUCACACCCCAAAUGCAUAAUCUCGUUAAUGAUUGAGGAGAGAAAAGGAUCAGAUUGCUGUUUUCUACAAUGGAGCAGGAUAUUGCUGAAGUCUCCUGGCAUAUGUUACCGAAUCAACUGGCCUUCCAGAGGCUAAGAAAUUUCUGUUAGUAAAAGAUGUUCUUUUUCCCA